AUGCCUCACAGCACACUUUCCAGGCUGAGCAUUUCCUUUUGUGCAUCCUCUCCAAGCCCUGAACUUACUCCAGUUGGCCUCUCCAGACCAAGCUCUCCCUCCCAGUGGCCUCUACAGGCCAAAAUUGUCCUCAGGUCAGCCUCUCCAGGGCCAACUCCUAGCUACCGGUGGCUUCUGCAGGCCAAAAUCGACCUCAAGUCAGCCUCUUCACACCCAGCUCUUGCCUCUGAGUGGCCUCUCCAGGAGCAAAACUUUCUCAAGUCGGCCUCUCCAGGCCCAGCCUCCUGCUUCCCGAGGGCAUGUACAGGCCCAGCCUCUGCCUCACAGCAGACUCUUCACACCCAGCUCUUCCCUGUCUGCGGCCUCUCCAGUCCAAAGCUGCUCCUGCCUUUUGGCAGCUUGUACAGGCCCAGCUCCUCCCUCACGGUGGCCUCUUUCGGCCCAACUCAUGCCUCUUGCAACGUGCCCAAGUGUCAGCUCCUGCCUCACACUGGCCUGUUGAGGCCCAGCUCAUGCCUCUCGUGGCCUCAACGGGCCCAUCCCCUGCCUGUCGGCGGCCUCUACAGGCCCGGCCUCUACCUCACAGUGGGCUCUCCAGGCCCACCUCUUCCUCACCGUGGCCUCCUGGGGCAAUGCUCCUCCCUCUCGGGAGCCUCUGUGGGCCCAGCUCCUGCCUCCCAGUGGCCUCUGCUGGCCAAGCCCGUGCCUCAGGGCAGCCUUUCCAGGCCUAGCGUUUGCUGCUUUGCAUCCUCUCCAGGCCCUGGACUUCCUCCAGUCGGCCUCUCCAGGCCCAGCUCUUCCUCUCGGCGGCCUCUGCAGGCCCAGACUGUCGUCAAGUCGGCCUGUCCAGGGCCAGCUCCUGCCUCCCGGCGGCCUCUGCAGGCCCAAGUCGUCCUCAAGUUGGCCUCCCCAGGCCCAGCAACGGCCUCUCGGCGGCCUUUCCGGGUGCAAAAGUUCCUCGAGUCAGCCUCUCCAGGCCCAGCUCCUCCUGCCUCCCAGUGGCCUCUUUCGGCCCAGCCCAGCUCAUGCCUCCCGGCGGCCUUCCCAGGCCCUGCUUUUGACUUUCGGUGGCCUCUGCAGGCCUCGACAAGGCCAGGCCUCCUGCCUCCCAAAGGCCUGCACAGGCCCAGCCUCUGCCUCACAGCAGACUCUCCACGCCCAGCUAGCUCUCGCCUCACUGCGGCUUCCCGAGUCCAAAGCUCCUGCCUCUCAGCCGCUUCGGCAGGCCCAGCUCCCGCCUGCCAGUGGCCUCUUCAGGCCCAUGGGGCUCAUUCCUCACAACGGCCUUUCCAGGCCCAGUUUUUCCCUUCCGGCGGCCUCUCCGGGCCCAGAACCUCCUCAAGUCGGCCUCUCCAGACCCACUUGCAGCCUCCGGGCGUCCUCUCUGGGCCCAGCUCUUCCUCCCGGCUGCUCUCCAGGCCCGACUCCUGCCUCUCAACAACCUUUUUGGACUCAGUGCCUACCCAUCUCCUGGCGGCCUUGGUCGGCCCACAGCUUCCUCAAGCCAAGCUCCCCAGGCCCAGGUCAGGCCUCACGGUGGCCUCUCCAGGAUGAGCUCCUGCCCUCCGAUGGCAUCUGCAGGCCCCAAAUGGUCUCCGGUCGGUGGGCUCCUCCACGCCAAGCUUGGGCCUCCCGGCGACCUCUGCAGACCCAAGUUGUCCUGAAGUCGGCCUCUCCCGGUCCUGCCUCCCAGCAAGUAAGCAAGCUCUUUUGGCUCAACUCCUGCCCAGCUCCCAACCGCCUUUGUAGGCCCCGAACUUUCUCCAGCCAAGUUCUUCGGGCCUAAUUCCUGCCGCCCGGUGGCCUGUACAGGCCCAGCACUGGUUGGAGAACAGCCUCUGCAGGCCCCGCGCUUGCCUCCCAGGGGCCUCUCCAGGCCCAGCUCUUGCCCCCAUGGCGGCCUCCCGGGGCCAAGUCCCUGCCUGCCUCCCGGCAGCCCGCGUGCGGCCCAGCUCCUCCCUCACGGUGGCCUGUUGAUGCCCAACUCAUGCCUCUGGCACCCUGCCCAGAGGCGUGAGCCCUUGCCUCACACCGGCCCCUCCCAUGCUGACAGAGGUCAGCCUGAGCCCCUAUUCUCACACCGGCCCCUCCCAGGCUGACAGAGGUCAGCGUGAGCCCCUGC